AGUGCGCCCAACAGCGGACUCCGAGACCAGCGGAUCUCGGCAAACCCUCUUUCUCGACCACCCACCUACCAUUCUUGGAACCAUGGCGGCAGUGGCGGCGGCCUCGGCUGAACUGCUCAUCAUCGGCUGGUACAUCUUCCGCGUGCUGCUGCAGGUGUUCCUGGAAUGCUGCAUUUACUGGGUAGGAUUCGCUUUUCGAAAUCCUCCAGGGACACAGCCCAUUGCGAGAAGUGAGGUGUUCAGGUACUCCCUGCAGAAGCUGGCAUACACGGUGUCGCGGACCGGGCGGCAGGUGUUGGGGGAGCGCAGGCAGCGAGCCCCCAACUGAGGCCCCAGCUCCCAGCCCUGGGCGGCCGUAUCAUCAGGUGCUCCUGUGCAUCUCGGCCAGCACGGGAGCCAGUGCCGCGCAGGAAUGUGGGGUCCCCUGUGUUCCCUCGCCAGAGGAGCACUUGGCAAGGUCAGUGAGGGGCCAGUAGACCCCCGGAGAAGCAGUACCGACAAUGACGAAGAUACCAGAUCCCUUCCCAACCCCUUUGCACCGGUCCCACUAAGGGGCAGGGUCGAGAGAGGAGGGGGGAUAGGGGGAGCAGACCCCUGAGAUCUGGGCAUAGGCACCGCAUUCUGAUCUGGACAAAGUCGGGACAGCACCAUCCCAGCCCCGAAGCCAGGGCCAUGCCAGCAGGCCCCACCAUGGAAAUCAAAACACCGCACCAGCCAGCAGAAUGGACAUUCUGACAUCGCCAGCCGACGCCCUGAAUCUUGGUGCAGCACCAACCGCGUGCCUGUGUGGCGGGACUGGAGGGCACAGUUGAGGAAGGAGGGUGGUUAAGAAAUACAGUGGGGCCCUCUCGCUGUCCCUUGCCCAGGGCACUUGCAUUCCAGCCUCGCUGCAUUUGCUCUCUCGAUUCCCCUUUCCUCCUCACUGCCUCCCAAGCCCACCCUACUCCAAAAUAAUGUGUCACUUGAUUUGGAACUAUUCAAGCAGUAAAAGUAAAUGAAUCCCACCUUUACUAAAACACUUUCUCUGAACCCCCCUUGCCCCUCACUGAUCUUGCUUUUCCCUGGUCUCAUGCAGUUGUGGUCAAUAUUGUGGUAAUCGCUAAUUGUACUGAUUGUUUAAGUGUGCAUUAGUUGUGUCUCCCCAGCUAGAUUGUAAGCUCCUGGAGGACAGGGACCACCUCUACAAAAAAUAAAAAAAGUACCUCCCCUGUCUCGCACAGUGUCCCAGGACCCUGCGGUGCAGUAGAGGCGCACCAAAA